GCCACAUUAUAACUAGUAGGGGAUCCUCACCGACCAUGGCCACAGCUGCCUCGAAUCCCUACAGCAUUCUCAGUUCCACCUCCCUAGUCCAUGCGGACUCUGCGGGCAUGCAGCAGGGGAGUCCUUUCCGCAACCCUCAGAAACUUCUCCAAAGUGAUUACUUGCAGGGAGUUCCCAGCAAUGGGCAUCCCCUCGGGCAUCACUGGGUGACCAGUCUGAGCGACGGGGGCCCAUGGUCCUCCACACUGGCCACCAGCCCCCUGGACCAGCAGGACGUGAAGCCCGGGCGCGAAGACCUGCAACUGGGUGCGAUCAUCCAUCACCGCUCGCCACACGUAGCCCACCACUCACCGCACACUAACCACCCCAACGCCUGGGGGGCCAGCCCGGCACCGAACCCGUCUAUCACGUCAAGCGGCCAACCCCUCAACGUGUACUCGCAGCCUGGCUUCACCGUGAGCGGCAUGCUGGAACACGGGGGACUCACCCCACCUCCAGCUGCCGCCUCUGCACAGAGCCUGCACCCGGUGCUCCGAGAGCCCCCGGAUCACGGCGAACUGGGCUCGCACCAUUGCCAGGAUCACUCCGACGAGGAGACGCCAACCUCUGAUGAGUUGGAACAGUUCGCCAAACAAUUCAAACAAAGAAGAAUCAAGUUGGGCUUCACGCAGGCCGACGUGGGGUUGGCGCUGGGCACACUGUAUGGUAACGUGUUCUCGCAGACCACCAUCUGCAGGUUCGAGGCCUUGCAGCUGAGCUUCAAAAAUAUGUGCAAGCUGAAGCCCCUGCUGAACAAGUGGCUGGAGGAGGCGGAUUCGUCCACAGGGAGCCCGACCAGCAUUGACAAGAUCGCUGCACAGGGCCGCAAGCGCAAGAAGCGGACCUCCAUCGAGGUGAGUGUCAAGGGCGUACUGGAGACGCAUUUCCUCAAGUGUCCCAAGCCUGCCGCGCAGGAGAUCUCCUCGCUGGCAGACAGCCUCCAGUUGGAGAAGGAAGUGGUGCGUGUCUGGUUCUGUAAUCGAAGACAAAAAGAGAAAAGAAUGACUCCGCCAGGGGAUCAGCAGCCGCAUGAGGUUUAUUCGCACACCGUGAAAACAGACACAUCUUGCCAUGAUCUCUGACUGGAGGAAGCGAGGAGGCGGCCGGCCGCACUGGGAGCAGCGCGGAUUUCUCUUUCUCUCUCACUCUCUUCCUUUCAUUCUAGUAUUCUUUAUUAUUUUUCUCUCUCUCUCGUUCGCUCGCUCUCUCGUACUCUCUCUCUUUUCCCUCCUUUCCUUUUUCUUUCCUUUCCCCUUUUUCUUUCCCUUCUUUUUCCCUUUCCUUUCCUUUCAUUUUCUUUCCUUUCCCCUUCCCUUCCCUUCCCUUCCAUCUCUUCCUUUCCUUUCCUUUCUUUUCUUUUGCUUUCCUUUCCUUUUUUUCCCUUUUCUUUCCUUUUCAUAAGAGGUUCUAACUUCUGUUGACAAAGGAAACACAUACUCUCUCAUUCAGGCUUCUCAAUGCUGAUACACAGUUACAUUAAGCAGUCCAAGCUGGGAUCUCAUAUUCCUGGCUCCCCGGGCAACAGUUCCCUUUAGCCUUUUCUGCUGAUCAAUACAUAUUGUUUACUCAGAGUAAGGUUUGUUUGGUCGCUCCUCUCUAGGAAGAACAAGGAGUGGGAUAACGUGGGGGCGGGGUGGGGCGGGGGAGGGAUUGGGAAGACAGAUGUGUGCCUCUGAAUAACCUUUCAGCGCCUUGGUUAUAGCAGCUGUAUUUCAGGUGAAAUUUGUUUUACAAUAGACUAGUUUUGCAUUUUUAAAAACUUCUAUAGCGUUUCUAAAUGUCUGCGGUGUUUUACUACAAUCUGUACACAAUAUUUGUGAGAUAAUUUGUAUCUAAUCGACCACUCCAUGUUAUUAUUGCUAUUAUUAUUACUACUUCGUUGAGCUGAUGGCUUUUUAAUUGCUUAGAAAAGGGAGGAGAUGAAUGGGAAUAGGCGGGGAGAGAGAUGCCUAUCUACUCACCGCCCCCCCCCUUCCCAAAUCUCUAUGAGGAGGAGAGGAUACAACGAAGAGAGUUAUUGAUGAUGAUAUUGGUUAUAUUUUUUUUCCGGGGUGGAGUGCCUAGGAAGGGCAGAAUAGGGAAGCCUAUUAGGUUUGCAAACUAGUGCGAAGUAGCAGCGGCGAUUUCGCAGCUUUCUGCCCUCCCUCCUGGAAGUGUGGAGCCCGCGCAGGCUACCGCAGCAUAGAUCGAGGUAUCUGAGAAGGAUUCGGCGGCAACUCUGGGCCAAAGAGGUGGCCUGACAGUCUGGGAGGGCUCCGCACUCACCGGACUCCAGGAUUCCUGCGCGCAGAAAUCCAGGCCCCCAGCCUCGCUAGGGCGACCUUCCGCGCGACCUCACUUCGGCCCUCCUAGAGGAAAGACUUUGCCUUCACACGCGAUUACUUUCACUGGAGAUCACGACCCGGAGACGCUGGCGACUGGGCCAGCGCCUCCCAUUUCGGUUCACCUCCAGUUCACCGCCCCCUCUGAGUAAGAAACCCUUGGGGAGGGGUGGCGAGGGAGUGGGGGAUAGGCAUUCUCUGCUCAGUGCAGAACGGCAAUGAAAUGAUUGGCAAAGGUCACAGGGAUUCUGGUCCAUCCGCGUACCACCUCUCCCCCCAUGUAUAUACCGCUGUCUGUGUGUGGGCUCGUGGGGAGCUGUCUCGGCGUUUCUGAUAAGCACAGCUGGUGGAAGCCCACAGCGACGAUCCAGCGAGCUAGCGAGCGCCCGGGAGGCUGGGUUCCUGCUUUUUAAAAUAUAAAUAUAUAUAUAUUUUUAAAUCUCUGUGUGUAUGUGUCUCUGUGCGUGUGUGUGUGUGCGUGCGCGUGCAAACGUGUGUGUGUAGAUAGCUGUGUGUAUCGCGUUACUAUGUACAAAAACAAAAAGUACAAAAAAAAAAAAAAACCUGGCUAGGCUGUGUAGAGAUCCCAAAAAUAUGCAGUUGCUGUGGCUUUAUUGCUAGCUAGUAUCCACACACCAGGUCCACAGGCGAACCUCAUUCCCAAGGAGCACACACGUGUGAGGCCGGCCAAGCACCCAACACCCAGCCGCCGCCGGCCAGACCUGGCUGGGGGCGCUGCACGCCACUGCUGGCCGCCUAGUCCGGCCUUUAGGCGCAGCUGCUGUAGACAAAGCUUCAAACUACCUAAGGACCAGAAAGCCCGGCCCGGUUGUCGAGGAUGCGUUAGUAUGAGUUGCCAGGCCUCUGGUCCACCACACUGUGUCUCCCUCAGCUGCAGGUCGAAGAGCAUGUGUUAAUUCAAAUCCCGGACCCUUCUACUUUUUUGUCAAGUCUCUGCAUUCUGUUGGUAGUUAGGUUUUAGUUCUGGGAUUUUAUUUUUUUUUCCCCCACACUGAGUUCAUGUUUUACAACUGUUGGGAGUUUUUUGUUUGUUUCGAUUUUUUUUCUUUGCAGUUAAUUGCUAUGGUUCGAACCUGAGUUAACCCAAAUAUUUCUGCCGACUUUAUAACUGUACAGUUUUGUAUAUUAAACGUUUUUGAAGUUAUUAAUUUAAAGAAAGAUCAUUUAGUUUAUUCAUUUAGUAACUGAUGUAUAAUAAACGCUAUUUUCAUUAAGAGUUGCUUUUUCAACUAUUUUAUUCAAAUUGCCUAUUGCAGUUGCCAACAAUUAUUUAUUUUCAAUAAAUUCUGCAUUGUGUUUAAAAGGAAAUUCUUUCACAGAUAAGUUGGAUGUCAAAAAGAAAACAAUUCGCUGUAAUGUUUGAUGUGAAGUUUUAGUCAAGGGGUUUAUAUUGACGCAAUAUUUUAUUGUUGUAAAAGAUUAAAAAGGUUUAAAUAAAACAUUUUUCCAAAAAAAAA